ACCGUCCGCGUUUGGCCGGCCGUGGGGAAGGAAGAAAGGAGCCAAGGAGGCGAGGCAUGGAUCCGCAGCCUCCUCCACCCGCCCAGGGCAGCCCACCUCACCGUGGCCGAGGCCGGGGCCGUGGCCGAGGCCGUGGUCGGGGCCGUGGCCGUGGCAGGGGGGGCGCUGGAGCCCCUAGGGCGCCCCUGCCCUGCCCCACCUGCGGCCGCCUCUUCCGUUUCCCCUACUACCUCUCCCGGCACCGGCUGAGCCACUCGGGGCUCCGGCCCCACGCCUGCCCGCUGUGCCCCAAGGCCUUCCGCCGGCCGGCCCACCUUUCCCGCCACCUGCGCGGCCACGGGCCCCAGCCCCCGCUGCGCUGCGCCGCCUGCCCCCGCACCUUCCCAGAACCGGCCCAGCUCAGGCGCCACCUGGCUCAGGAGCACGCGGGCGGCGAGGUCGAGCUGGCCAUCGAGAGGGUGGCCAAGGAGACGGCCGAACCCAGCUGGGGCCCGCAGGACGAGGGCUCGGAGCCGCCCACCACCGCUGCAGCAGGGGCCACGGAGGAGGAGGCGGUCGCAGCGUGGCCUGAGACGUGGCCUGCGGGGGAGCCUUCCACGCUGGCUGCGCCCACCAGCGCCGCGGAGCCCCGGGAGUCGGAGUCGGAGGAGGCCGAGGCCGGGGCAGCAGAGCUGAGGGCCGAGCUGGCGCUGGCGGCCGGGCGGCAGGAGGAGAAACAGGUCCUGCUCCAGGCAGACUGGACGCUGCUGUGUCUGCGCUGCCGCGAAGCCUUCGCCACCAAGGGCGAGCUCAAGGCGCACCCGUGUCUGCGCCCCGAGGGCGAACAGGAAGGGGAAGGGGGGCCCCCGCCACGCCCCAAGCGACACCAGUGCUCCAUCUGCCUCAAGGCCUUCGCCAGGCCCUGGUCCCUGUCGCGCCACCGGCUGGUCCACUCCACCGACCGCCCUUUCGUGUGCCCAGACUGCGGCCUGGCCUUCCGCCUCGCCUCCUACCUCCGCCAGCACCGCCGCGUCCACGGCCCCCUCAGCCUGCUGGCCCCGCUGCCCGCGGCGGGCAAGAAGGACGACAAGGCCUCGGGUGCACGGAACUCAGCCAAGGGGCCGGAGGGGGGCGAGGGGGCGGAGUGCGGGGGUGCCUCGGAAGGGGGAGAAGGGCAGAACGGAGGCGACGCCGCCCCGGCUCGGCCCCCCGCCGGGGAGCCCCGCUUCUGGUGCCCAGAGUGCGGCAAAGGUUUCAGGCGCCGGGCGCACCUGCGGCAGCACGGGGUGACCCACUCGGGAGCGCGCCCCUUCCAGUGCGUGCGCUGCCAGCGGGAGUUCAAGCGCCUGGCCGACCUGGCGCGCCACGCACAGGUGCACGCGGGGGGCCCAGCCCCGCACCCGUGCCCCCGCUGCCCGCGCCGCUUCUCGCGCGCCUACAGCCUCCUGCGCCACCAGCGCUGCCACCGCGCAGAGCUGGAGAGGGCCGCCGCGCUGCAGGCACUGCAGGCCCAGGCCCCGACGUCGCCGCCACCGCCCCCGCCGCCCCUGAAGGCCGAGCAGGAGGAAGAAGGGCUCCCGCUGCCCCUCGCAAACAUUAAGGAAGAGCCGCCCUCUCCGGGGACCCCACCCCAGUCCCCGCCGGCUCCCCCUGUCUUCCUCAGCGCCUCCUGUUUCGACAGCCAAGACCACUCAGCCUUCGAGAUGGAGGAGGAAGAGGUAGACAGCAAGGCUCACCUGCGCGGGCUGGGGGGCCUGGCCUCCUGACCUUCGCCGCCCUGCCCUCCGCCGCUCCGCCUGAGCUCCCCGGUUUGCAGAAUGGAGGAGGGAAGUUGAAGGAGCCACCUCCUCUGUCUACCCACCCGUCCCCUUCACGCCCUUGACACUAAGGAGUGGGGGGCCCUGGACUGCCCCUUCCUCCCCCAUCGCCCGCCCCCAGAACCCCUGAUGCUGGUUAGGAACCGCUCACCCCAACAUGUGUCUUAAGGCAGGACGACUUGGAAAAAAAGGCGGCGGACAGUUGGCCAGAGGGAUGGAGACUGGUGGGGACGCCCCCGCCUCCCUGUCCCCCGUUUCACACACUGGACACCAUCACCUCUUUGGAACUGCCAGACCCUGGGGGUCCCCAGUGAGCAAAGGUCUGUCCUUGUCCCUUUGUCUGUCUGUGAAUAAAUGUGAGUUCGUGAAAUCCAAGAGAGCGAGGUGUUCUGUGGAGGUGGGGCAGGCUGGGGGCGCUGGGGCGAGUCAGGAUUUGUCCAGCCAACUCUGAACUUGGGUUCAGAGCAGGAAGGACACAGAUGCAUCAGAAAAUAUGUGGCCCUCAACCAAGCAAGAAGCCGGUGAAGGCUGGGUUGAGAAGAAACAGGAAUGUGAGAAGAUAGAUCAUCGUCACCGCUGCCCUGUGGAAGCUCCGCGCGAUUAUCCUCACCACUGCCCUGUGGAAGCUCCGCGCCUUACUCAGUCAAUCUCUACCACACCCUUACUCUGUGUCAGCGGUGGUACUAGGCACUGAGGAGGAGUCCAAUACCUUCCUCUGAAAGAGCUGGAAUUCUAGCCCUGCAUUGUCCAACAUAACUUUUUUUUUUUCUCAGAAAAGUUUCCAUAAUCUUUCUUCCCUCACUCUGUUGCCCAAGCUGCAGUGCCGUGGUGCAGUCAUAGCUCACUGCAGUCUCAAACUCCCAGACCCAAGCAAUCCUCUUAGCCUCUCAAGGAGCUAGGACUACAGGUGCAUGCCACCACACCCAGCUGAUUGUUUCAUUUCUUGCAGAGACGGAGUCUUGCUAUCUUGCCCAGUCUGGGAGAACUUUUUGUGAUGAUGGGAUAUUCUACAUCUUCACUGUCCAAUAUGAUAUCCAGCAGACACACGUGGCUAUUUCCGUUUAAAUUUAGAAUAUGGAAAUGUAAAGACAUUAAGAUGAAAUAAAUGUAAAAGUUCGGUUCCUCA